AUGGGGAGACUGACAGACGGGGAGCUGUAUAGGGCCAGAUUCCGGUCCAUGGUGGUAACCCCAUCCCCCACCACUGCAGAUGCGGCACAAAGCCAGCUGCCACAGGAGGUGCACUGCCCCACGGGCAGCUGUGCUCACCUGCGUGGCGUCCGCAGGAAGCCCUCAGACCCUGGCCAGCCUGGUCUCUGCUUCUCACUCCAGGCUCAAGGCUGGCUGCUAUUCCAUUCACCCCAUUCCCUUUCCCUCAGGCCAGAAGCAUCACUCACAACUCCAGACCCUUGCACACCAAUCUCCUCACUCAGUUCACCCUCAGAUGUCCAACUCCACAUGGCCAAAACCGAGACCAGUCUCACUCCAAGCUCAUCCACCCGCCUAGCUGCCCAAGCUGAAAUCCACAGUUGCCCUGUACGACCCCCCGACCCCCCACCUCACCCCCCAGCUCACCUCAAACCUCAUCAGUCCCUCUGCUCACAGCCUGCACAGCCACCACCCAGUCUGGGCACCAUACCUCUCUGGGCAACCCCCAUGGCCCCCAGCCAGUCUUCCAGCUCCCACCCUGACUCCAGUGAGCUGCCAGAGGGAUCCUUGAAAAAUGCUCUGGAAGCCAAGGUGGGCGGAUCACGAGAGCCUUUGCACUGGCGAUGCCAUCUGCUGCCUGGAUGUCUUCCUGCUGGCUGGUCCCGUUGCAUGGUAGCCUUAGGUGUCUCCUCAGAGAGGUCCCUCGCUGACCAUCAGGCUCCUCACUCCCUGUCGUAUCCCCUUCACCAAAGAUUCCCAUUCCCUGACGACGCCUGUCCCCUCGGAAUGCAGGCCUCGUGGGAAUUCAGCCCAUCCGCAAGUGCAGUGGCAGGGCGGCCCCCUUCCCCCUUGACGACGCCUGUCCCCUUGGAAUGCAGGCCUCGUGGGAAUUCAGCCCAUCUGCAAGUGCAGUGGCAGGGCGGCCCCCUUCUCCCUUGA